ACUUCCGGUAGGAGCCUCGCAGGAAUGGUCUCCGGGUAGAGGCAGGUAAGGAUGUCCCGGGCCGGUGGAGAAGGAAGAGCUGGGCGUGUGGCUUCGCUUGGAAUCCGAAUCAGAGCUUGGACCAGAGCCUUCCCUGAGAAUGCUGAAGCAACACCUUCUUUGGAUUGAGUUUCUUCCAGAGGGAACGAAGAAGAGGAUUAAAUAAUACAUUCAAUUCUAAAAUAAGACAUGGCCCAUGAGUUGGUGAUGUUCAGAGAUGUGGCUAUAGAUGUCUCUCAGGAGGAAUGGGAAUGCCUGAACCCAGCGCAGAGGAAUUUGUACAAGGAGGUGAUGUUGGAGAAUUAUAGCAACUUGGUGUCACUUGGCUAGAGUGCAAUGGCGUGAUCUCGGCUCACCACAACCUCUGCCUCCCAGCUUCAAGCAAUUCUCCUGCCUCAGCCUCCCGAGUAGCUGUGAUUACAGGACUUUCUGUUUCUAAGCCAGCCGUAAUCUCCUCAUUGGAGCAAGGGAAGGAGCCCUGGAUGGUUGUGAGGGAAGAGACAGGAAGAUGGUGCCCAGACUUGGCAUCCAGAGAUGAGCCCCAGAAGUUAUCUCCAAAAAGGGAUAUUUAUGAAACAGAAUUAUCCCAGUGGGUUAACAUGGAAGAAUUUAAAAGCCAUAGUCCUGAGAGAUCAAUUUUCAGCGCUAUCUGGGAAGGCAACUGUCAUUUUGAGCAACAUCAGGGACAAGAGGAGGGUUAUUUUAGACAACUUAUGAUUAACCAUGAAAACAUGCCCAUUUUUAGCCAACAUACUUUACUCACUCAAGAAUUUUAUGAUAGAGAGAAAAUCUCUGAAUGUAAAAAGUGUAGAAAAAUCUUCAGUUACCAUUUAUUUUUUAGUCACCACAAAAGAACUCAUUCUAAAGAACUUUCUGAAUGUAAAGAAUGCACAGAAAUUGUUAAUACACCAUGCCUUUUUAAACAACAGACAAUUCAAAAUGGUGACAAAUGCAAUGAGUGUAAAGAAUGUUGGAAGGCCUUUGUUCAUUGCUCACAACUUAAACAUCUAAGAAUUCAUAAUGGUGAAAAACGCUAUGAAUGUAACGAAUGUGGGAAGGCCUUUAAUUAUGGCUCAGAACUUACUCUACAUCAAAGAAUUCACACUGGUGAGAAACCUUAUGAAUGUAAAGAAUGUGGGAAGGCCUUUAGACAGCGAUCACAGCUUACUCAACAUCAGAGACUUCAUACUGGUGAAAAACCCUAUGAAUGUAAGCAAUGUGGGAAGGCUUUUAUUCGUGGCUUUCAACUUACUGAACACCUGCGACUCCAUACUGGAGAGAAACCUUAUGAAUGUAAAGAAUGUGGAAAGACUUUUAGGCAUCGCUCACAUCUUACUAUACAUCAGAGAAUUCAUACUGGUGAGAAACCCUAUGAAUGUCGGGAAUGUGGGAAGGCCUUUAGCUAUCACUCAAGCUUCUCACACCAUCAGAAAAUUCAUUCUGGCAAGAAACCUUAUGAAUGUCAUGAAUGUGGGAAGGCUUUUUGUGAUGGCUUACAACUAACCCUACAUCAGAGGAUUCAUACUGGUGAGAAACCCUAUGAGUGUAAGGAAUGUGGGAAGACUUUUAGACAGUGUUCACACCUCAAAAGACAUCAGAGAAUUCAUACUGGUGAGAAACCUCAUGAAUGCAUGAUAUGUGGUAAGGCCUUUAGACUUCAUUCACACCUUAUUCAACAUCAAAGAAUUCAUACUGGUGAGAAACCCUAUGAAUGUAAGGAAUGUGGGAAGGCCUUUAGCUAUCAUUCAAGCUUCUCACACCAUCAGAGAAUUCAUUCUGGAAAGAAACCUUAUCAAUGCGGGAAGGCGUUUAAUCAUAGAUUACAACUUAACUUACAUCAGACUCUUCAUACUGGCGAGAAGCCAGUCAGGUUUCCUCUCCUCCCUCCCCAUCCUAGUCUAGCAUCAUGAAAUUUGUUGAUGGAAAUAUACAUUGUCUUUGUUUUAUUUAAGGAAAAAGUUGGUAAGCCACCAGUUUCAUUAGUAUUUAUUUAUUUAAAUAAUCCUUGAAAAUCAAAUGUUUUUAAGUGAGAAAGUGGAUAACUAAAGUGUAAAUUUUGGUCUCAUUUUAAUGCUGUUUCUGAGUUAUUGUAUUAACCAUUAUUGAGAAUAAAUUUUUUUAUUGAGAAUAAAUUUUCUAAAAUUACAUGUUUCACUGAAACCAGUGAAAUAUUUCACUGAAACAGUGAAAUAAAAUGAAAACAAUUUCCUCCCUUCCCUCAAAUCUCUGAGAUAACCAGUAUGUGUAUUUCUUCUUCCUUUAUGCUCAAACAACCUGUACACAGAAAGCAUUUUUUGCAUGUGUUUGGAGGAGCUUUUACCCCCAUACAGACAUUUGACAGCGUCUUGUCCUUUUCAUAAUAAUCAUGAAUACUUUUCCAGGUCAGUACGUAAAGAUGUAACCCAUUCUUUGUAAGGUUCAGAAUAUUUCUAGAAUGGAAUGUAUGUCCGUAUUUUGGGCCAUUACCUACUACAGACAUUGAAGUUGUUUCUAAUGUUCACCUAGAACUCUAAUUUUACCUUCUUUUGUUUCUAUUGUGCAGAUUCCCAACAGUGGGAUUAAAGAGUAUCUGGCGUAUAUAUUUUGACAUUACAUUUAUUUUUUAAAAUCUUCUAAAUUUUUUGUUUAAUAAAAGCACACAUUAUAAAAAUUCAAAAAUUACCAAAAAUGUGAAAAUUAAUUCUCCCCUAACAUCCAGUUCUGUAGCCACUCACUUUCCACAGAUGCAACAACUGCUAUCAGUUUCCUUUUAUUCUAACGGGAAUAUUUCAUGUAAAUUUCAUAAAUUCUUUGGACAAAAGUAGGUUAUUCAUAAUAUGUGAUUUAUUACACAUUCUCAUUAUUAGUCCACAUUUGGCCUACUUCAUUUUUUUUUUUUUUGAGACACACCCAGGCUGGAGUCCAGUGGUGCAAUCUUGGCUCACUGCAACCUCCGCCACCCAGGUUAAAAAUUCUCCUGCCUCAGCCUCCUGAGUAGCUGGGACUACAGGCAUGCGCAGCCACUAUGCCCGGCCAAUAAGCUAUAUUUAUUCUUAUUUGAUGUGGAUGAAAAUUAUCAAAAUUGGCCAGGCUUGGUGGCUCAUGCCUGUAAUCCCAGCACUUUGGGAGGCCGAGGCGGGCGGAUCACGAGGUCAGGAGAUCGAGACCAUCCUGGCUAACAUGGUGAAACCCCGUCUCUACUAAAAAAAAAAUACAAAAAUUAGCUGGGCGUGGUGGUGGGUGCCUGUAGUCCCAGCUACUCGGGAGGCUGAGGCAGAAGAAUGGCGUGAACCUGGGAGAUGGAUCUUGCAGUAAGCUGAGAUCGCGCCACUGCACUCCAGCGUGGGCAACACAGUGAGACUCUGUCUCAAAAAGAAAAAAAAAAAAGAAAAUUGUCAAAACACAACCAAUAGAUAAUGUUAACAUGCAUUCUAACAUGCAAUUUAUUGGAUUUAGCGAAUAGAAUGUGAGUGGAAGUUACUUUUGGUAGAACUGUUGGGAAAAGGGCUUGUGGAGUGCCUGCAUAAACUGGCCAUAAAAAUAUGGGACAAUAAGUUGUGGAAAGCCACAAGAGGCCUCUGAGGAGGAAAGCCUCCUAAUUGCCAUCACGUUCCUAUGACCAGAGUGUGACCUGCUCUCUUAUCUAUAAACACUGUGCUCAAGGAGAAAGACACUCCUUUGAAGCAUUGGAAUGUGGCCAGAUAUGCUGGCUUCUAGUUAGGCCCACUCCCCACAGCUGCUCUCUGAUAAGUAAAAGAAUAAAUCAGUAGUUAAGUUUAUGCUGCUUCAGCACAAAGAAAAUGUACCUAAACUGCCAUUGCCCCCCUUUCACUGUUUCACCCCUGAACAUCUGCUUCUUAGAUCUAAGUGAUUGUACUCAAUAAAUAGUGUGGAGACCAGAGCUUGGCGCCUUUGCAGCUUUUGAUUUGCUCUGGCCCCUUGGCUCCCACCUUUAUGAACUCUUAA